AUGAAUUGGGUAAAUGACAGCAUCAUACAGGAGUUUAUUCUGCUGGGUUUCUCAGAUCGACCUUGGCUGGAGUUUCCACUCCUUGUGGUCUUCUUGAUUUCUUACACUGUGACCAUCUUUGGCAAUCUGACCAUUAUUCUAGUGUCACGCCUGGACACCAAACUUCAUACCCCCAUGUAUUUUUUUCUUACCAAUCUAUCACUCCUGGAUCUUUGUUACACCACAUGUACAGUCCCACAAAUGCUAGUAAAUUUAUGCAGCAUCAGGAAAGUAAUCAGUUAUCGUGGCUGUGUAGCCCAGCUUUUCAUAUUUCUGGCCUUGGGGGCUACUGAAUAUCUUCUCCUGGCCGUCAUGUCCUUUGAUAGGUUUGUAGCUAUUUGUCGGCCUCUCCAUUACUCAGUUAUCAUGCACCAGAGACUCUGCCUCCAGUUGGCAGCUGCAUCCUGGGUUACUGGUUUUAGUAACUCAGUGUGGUUGUCUACCCUGACUCUCCAGCUGCCACUCUGUGACCCCUAUGUGAUAGAUCACUUUCUCUGUGAAGUCCCUGCACUGCUCAAGUUAUCUUGUGUUGAGACAACAGCAAAUGAGGCUGAACUAUUCCUUGUCAGUGAGCUCUUCCAUCUAAUACCCCUGACACUCAUCCUUAUAUCAUAUGCUUUUAUUGUCCGAGCAGUAUUGAGGAUACAGUCUGCUGAAGGUCGACAAAAAGCAUUUGGGACAUGUGGUUCCCAUCUAAUUGUGGUGUCUCUUUUUUAUAGUACAGCCGUCUCUGUGUACCUGCAACCACCUUCGCCCAGCUCCAAGGACCAAGGAAAGAUGGUUUCUCUCUUCUAUGGAAUCAUUGCACCCAUGCUGAAUCCCCUUAUAUAUACACUUAGGAACAAGGAGGUAAAGGAAGGCUUUAAAAGGUUGGUUGCAAGAGUCUUCUUAAUCAAGAAAUAA